CAUUUGCUGCGCUACAGACGCGACCUUCUUGCUUCGCGAAGCGUCGUAAACUCCGAGGCUCCGCUCUGCGCUGCCGUCCUGGGCACACGGACUCGCGCCGCUCCCGGGGAGGGGAGAGAGCCAGGAACCUCCCGCUGCGGUCCAGGGUUGCCACGCGGACCCCAGAGGUUCCUGAAUCGCACUGAGCUCCCCGGAAAGGAAAGGACGUUCCCAGAGUUAGAGAAGAACGGAGAGCAAACUGAAGAGAGACCCCGUUCCCUUUAGCAGUCGGCUGGCCUGUUUCUCCAUCCCCCUCAGCCCUAAGCAAGCACGAAUCUACCUUUUGUCUUUAUUCUAGACACUGCAUGACUGGGCGUUCAUCAACACCAACAUCUUUGCCAGGACCAAGAUAGACCCCAGCGCCUUGGUGCAGAAGCUGGAGCUGGACGUGAGGAGUGUCACUUCCGUCAGGAGAGGUGAGGCAGGCUCGAGUGCACGGAGCGUCCCUUCCAUCAGGAGAGGUGCAGAGGCCAAGACCGUUUUGCCCAAGAAGGAGAAAAUGAAGCUGAGGCGUGAGCAAUGGUUGCAGAAAAUCGAAGCCAUAAAACUGGCUGAGCAGAAGCACAGGGAGGAGCGGAGGCGGAGGGCCACGGUGGUGGUGGGGGACCUGCACCCUCUCAGGGAUGCCCUGCCCGAGCUGCUGGGGCUCGAGGCUGGCAGCCGGCGCCAAGCCCGCAGCAGGGAGAGCAACAAGCCCCGGCCCUCAGAGCUCAGCCGGAUGAGCGCAGCCCAGAGACAGCAGCUUCUCGAGGAAGAAAGGACCCGGUUUCAGGAGCUGCUGGCCAGUCCGGCCUACAGAGCCAGCCCCCUGGUGGCCAUCGGGCAGACGCUGGCCCGGCAGAUGCAGCUGGAAGAUGGCGGCCAGCUCUGACCAGGGCAGCGGGCAUGCCACAACUCCUCAGGACACAUGUGGGCCAAGUAGAGAGCGCCGGCCCCUCAAGGACCAUGGCCUGAGCCUGGUGGACGCCCUUCCCUCUGGUCGGUUGUGGGGCUCAAUAAAUGGCUCUGUGAACUUCCCCUGCACUGCCAGGGCCGUUCCCA